GUUACUGUCCCGCGAACCCACAUCCCUACAAAGCAGGAAAGUAUGCUUGGGAGAGGCCAAGUGAGUGGGGAAUCAGCCCAAAGCCAGGCGUCCAGGGUCUCCCUCACCUGAAGCUGACUUUUUCCCCACCUUGGACAGAGGGCGGGAGAUGCCAUCCCCACUGAACCCAGUGCUUUCACCAGCCAUAUUAGCUCCCACUCACCCCCCGUCGUGGAAGCCUCGGCCGUCACACCUGCAGGGCCGGGGCGUGCAUGGCCUCAGGGAUGGCCUGUUCAGCUGCUGGGUGACUCGGGUCCAGGUGCCUCACCACCUGCUGAGCUCUGUGUGAUUUCUGGACACUUCUGCUCGUUGCCUUUGGGCUCAGUGAAGAGUCUGGAGUUUAUCUGGAGUGAGGUGGCCGGUUCUUGGUGGGAUCUGAGCAGGUAAGAAGCAGGGUCUUUCUUAUGUUUUAAGGAAAGCCCUGUGGCUGCUGGGUGGGGGACCAGCUGGAGGGGCAGGAGGGCAGCAGGUGACUCAUUACAAGGCUGGGGCCAUCAUCCUGUGAGAGCUGGGCAUGACCAGUGCAGGUCAGUGGGGUUGAGGGUACAGACCAGUGGGACCCACAGACGGCUCGGGAGUGACCAAGCCUCUGCUGAGCUGCCCAGGUCCCCUCUGGUGGACACCUCCUACCCGGAGCCCCCCAAGGUGGUGCCAAAGCUAGACCACCAUACAGCCAGAGGCCUCCAGGCCCUACCCACGACAGCCCAGCUGGCUUCUGCCCAGCCACCGUCACACACAGAGGGCAGCCGUCCCCAUGGUCCCUAGAGGCGGUUGAGGACCACUGUGCCUGGAGUCAUCUGUGGCUAUAAACCAGGAGGAGAAGGCUGCCCACCCCCUGCCCCAGAGAUGGGGAGGCUGGGGCCACCCGGUGGAUUUGGGCAGGUCCCAGCUUCCAGGAUCAUGAGGUGAAAACGUGAAGGGACCCUAGAGGCCAUGGGGACCCAGGCACAGAGCGGCGGCCUCUCAUCCUCCCCAUGGUCAAGGAGGUCAGUGCCUUCCCGGGGUGGAUUACGGAUGGUAGUAUCUUCCUUCUCCUCAGAGUCCAUUCAGGAGCAGGAAAGUUCAUCUCAGACCCUAAAUCCAGCCACGUCAUGCCACGCUUAACACCUCUAACAACUUCCCCUGGCACUUAGGACAGCGUCUGGCUCCUUCCCUCGGCUCAUGGCCCUCAGAAUCUGCGUCACAUACACCCCAGCUCUCCCGAUAGGUCUCUGCACUCGCUGUUGCCUCUGCCUGGAACAGUCUCCCUCCUGGUGUCAUUGUCUCCGUGGUGUGUCCUUCCUGACCUUCCACCUCCACCAGUCUGUCCCCCUUGGGGACAGGGACUCGUUGCUCAUGUUCACCCGGCAGGCUGGACACUUCGUGGAGGGCUCCAAAGCCGGCAGAUCCCGGGGCCGCCUCUGUCUCUCCCAGGCCCUGCGUGUUGCGGUGAGAGGAGCAUUUGUGUCUCUGUGGUUUGCUGCUGGAGCUGGUGACCGGGAGAGAAACAAGGGAGACAAGGGUGCCCAGACAGGUGCGGGGCUCAGCCAGGAGGCAGAAGACGUGGACGUGUCCCGGGCCAGGAGGGUCACAGAUGCACCACAAGGCACUCUGUGUGGCACUGGGAACAGGAAUUCUGGGAGUCAGUCUGCAAGGGUGGUGGGCGUUGCUCACCUGGGAGAAGCCUUUAGAGUGGGCGUUGAGCAGGCCAUUAGCUCGUGCCCUGAGGAGGUGCAUGGGCGGCAUGGGCUCUCCAUGGAAAUUAUGUGGGCGCGAAUGGAUGUGGCUCUGCGCUCACCUGGGCGAGGACUUCUGGCCGGUGCCGGGGCACUCUGCAUGACCCUGGCAGAAUCGAGCUGCCCUGACUAUGAAAGGGGAAGAAGAGCAUGCCUGACCCUCCACCGGCACCCCACCCCUCACUGCUCCACCUGGGGCCUGCCUCUGCGGGUGGCUGGGUCCUGGCUGACUGUUGUGACUGUUGAGGCCCUGGGGGGGUGGCGCAUGGGAGUUAGGAGGACUGGCCAGGUGGGGCCCACUAUGCACCCACCCCCAGUGUCAGGUGCUUCUCCUCUCCUCCUCCACCACCUCCUCCUCCUCCUCCUCAUCAUCAUCCUCACUUGUUGAGGACGUCCUGUGUGCCAAGUGGUUUAUAUGCCCAGCCUCAUUUAAUCCUCAGAAUGACUCCAUGAGGUAGCUACUAAAACCCCCCACUUAACAGAUGAGGAAACUGAGGCCUAGAGAAGCUCAACAAGUUGCCUAAGUUCCAAGUUUCCUCUCCCAACUCUCCUACCCUCUCCUCUUCCUUCUCCUUUCUCCCAUUCUUCCCUGCCUCUUCCCUAACUAGACAAUUUUUUAUUGAGUGUCUCCCAGGUGCAGGCAUGAGCCAGGUGCUGGGAAAAUCAUGAUAACCCAGCUCCUUCUGGUCAUUUUCUCAGCUGGUUAGAGGCUGGGAGGACACGCAAGUUCAGCUCCAGCCGACUGGGGCAUUGGUGGUAGCCCCUGGAGACAUUGUGCAAUGGGGCUACGAGGCUGCAUCUGGCUCCAGGGAAGCGUGUUGCAAUCCAUGAGUGAUGUCUGCCAUGCGUACAGGCAUGGAGAGUGAGGCGCCUGUACUGUCUUUCUGUAGACCCUAGACUGGUGGGGCCUCUGAAAUGCAUCCAGACACUGUGCUGGGUGUGUUGCAUGGCCCUCCCAACCAAUUCAGUAUUUUUCUCCCCAUUUUCCAGGGAGAAAUCUAAGGCGUCAGAAUGUAAGGUUCUUAUUGGAACCCAGGCUCCAGGGUCCCUGGUUUUCUGUGACAUCAUGCUGCAGGACCCUGUUUCUCUCUUUGCUUUGGCUGCUGGGGAGCUCAGAAGGGAGCUUUAGGCUUGCUCUCAGUCACCACAUUAGCUCAGGGGUUUGGGCAUUUUUGUCGCCGUCUCCUUUGGGCUCUGUCUCCUCCCUGCUGUGCUUCCUGAGGAGCAGGCCGGAUGUAAGUUAUCAACUAUAAAUAAAACCAAGACUUCCGUUCUGGCUCUCA